AGGCCCGGAUCCUGGCGGCCUGGGCGGCCGCACCAUGGACUCGGGAACCGAGGAGUACGAGCUCAACGGCGGCCUGCCUCCGGGCACACCCGGCUCCCCGGACGCCUCGCCCGCAGGUUGAAGGUUCCUGGGGCCACAUCUGGGCCGAGAGGCAUGGUCCUUGGAGCCGGCCCGCUGGGGCUGGAGGCACGGGCCCAUCAACGUGAACCAUUACGCCAGCAAGAAGAGCGCAGCCGAGAGCAUGCUGGACAUCGCGCUGCUGAUGGCCAACGCGUCCCAGCUGAAGGCCGUCGUGGAACAGGGCCCCAGCUUCGCCUUCUAUGUGCCCCUGGUGGUCCUCAUCUCCAUCUCCCUUGUGCUGCAGAUCGGCGUGGGGGUGCUGCUCAUCUUCCUUGUCAAGUACGACCUUAACAACCCGGCCAAGCACGCCAAGCUGGACUUCCUCAACAACCUGGCCACGGGCCUGGUGUUCAUCAUCGUGGUAGUCAACAUCUUCAUCACGGCCUUCGGGGUCCAGAAGCCCUUGAUGGACAUGGCACCCCAGCAGUAGGACACCCAGGACCCUGGAUGUUGCCUGCCCUGCAACUCAGCUGCCCGACCCCAGGAGUCGCCAUACCUGUGAGGUGUCCACCUCCCUGCACAUGGCACUACCCAGACUGCCAGAGCCCAGGCUGGCCUCAUCUGCACCAUGUCCCCGGACCAGCCCUUGCUCUGACUGCGGCCAAGCACCACGCAGGAGGCCACUCUUGUCUCUCAGCAGCUGUUCCCAGGAGGCAGCUCCCUCCUGGCACAUGGGGGCUGGCCACAAUAGCCCAGAGGGUCAGAACUGGACAGCUGCAGAGACCUGUGCCCAGAGAAGGGUCUCGACCCACUCAAGGACACACAGCAGGUCCGUGGAUGGGCUGGAUGAGUGACCAGGGCCAGCCUCUGUCUCAGGACAUUCCAGAAGGACAAGGAGAUGUCUCUCCCUCUCCCAAAGCACCAGCGUCCCUGCCUCCCGUGGGCCCUGUCCGGGUUGCCCUGGUGACCCCAGCCUCUGUCCACUUCCUAACCCAGGGACCCUGCACAGCCAGAACUGCCUUUGGCCCUACGGAUGGCCACUGGCUCUGGUCUUAAGUGCCUGGGCUUGGUGGCCAUCAAGAGGGAGCCAGUCAGGCCUGUGAGGGCCGUAGACCUUGUAUAUACCCUGCACCAGCAGUGACCGGGCAGAGCCCAACCCCCUCCACGGGGGUCCCAGCACCCACUUUUCUAAUCAUGAAUGAACAAUAAAGCCCACGCUCUUUGUCAGGCUCCA